AGACAGGAGCAGUCAUUCCCUUGUAGGGACAACUAGAAGGUAAGUCCUCUGGUAGAUCAGUUUCUUUCCAAAAUGGAGAGAACUAAAGAAGAGUCCCAGGUAAGACUGAUCAGUCUACAUCGAAGGUGCUAAUCCACUUAAGGUGGGCUGGGUAACUGGAAGGAUUAGUGCACAGUUGCUAUGAGAUGCAUCUGUGCCAGUGUGGCUCAUUGUCACACCUGGGCCCAGAGUCUCAUUGCAAGUUAAGGGACCGAAUUUGAAAAAGAUGCUAGGACAGUUAGAAGAUUAACAGACUGAGGUAGGUAACAGAAAUAAAUGUAAUAGGUUAGACCUAAAAACCUUUCAAUUUACACUUAAAAUAGGAAUUUAUGCAAAAGUGUUCGAUUCAUUAAUAUAGUAUCAAGUUUCUAAAUAUUUGAUUGAUUGGAUCAUUUUAGUAUUCUUAUCGCCUUCUUUUACCUUGUGGAGUAUCCAAGAAAUGUAGUCUCUUAGGUGACAUGUGAAAUACUUAAGUCCAUUUUGUUUACCAUUUCACAUACAAUUUUAAUAUUAUUUUAAACCAUGGAACUGUUCCAUUUUGGUAGAAUAUGUGUGUAUUUUGUGUGUGGCUUAUAGUUUUUAAAACAGAAGCCAAAUUGUCAUGAUGCAUAGGUUGUACCACCAUGGGGAUUUGUCUCUGAGGAUACUGUUAAACUUUUAUUUUUUUAAACUUAAGUAUUUUUAGUUAUUAGAUUUGAAAAUACAUUGUAGGGCAGUGUACUAACAGCCUUUGACAUUGGCCUAAUAGAACUGUCUUUGUUAUCUUCCUAGGUUGAAGCGAGCAGUUUCUUAUUCAAAGUGUCCUUGCUUCUCUUAGGCCAGGGCUUUUAUAAGGGCUUAGUGAGUACCUUAUAAAGGCUGACCCUUACUGGAGCAGAUUAUAGUGUAGCAUGAAGAGCUAAAUUUAGAGGGAAGUGGGGCCUCUGCUCCAAAUAGUAACAGCUAAAGGAUAGACACUCUUGGAGAGCAGAAUAUCUUUAUUUAGUCUGUCACCACCAGUGGAAAUUUUAUGAAUAAGCAUCAGAAGCCAGUGCUAACAGGCCAGCGGUUCAAAACUCGGAAAAGGGAUGAAAAAGAGAAAUUCGAACCCACAGUCUUCAGGGAUACACUUGUCCAGGGGCUUAAUGAGGCUGGUGAUGACCUUGAAGCUGUAGCCAAAUUUCUGGACUCUACAGGCUCAAGAUUAGAUUAUCGUCGCUAUGCAGACACACUCUUCGAUAUCCUGGUGGCUGGCAGUAUGCUUGCCCCUGGAGGAACGCGCAUAGAUGAUGGUGACAAGACCAAGAUGACCAACCACUGUGUGUUUUCAGCAAAUGAAGAUCAUGAAACCAUCCGAAACUAUGCUCAGGUCUUCAAUAAACUCAUCAGGAGAUAUAAGUAUUUGGAGAAGGCAUUUGAAGAUGAAAUGAAAAAGCUUCUCCUCUUCCUUAAAGCCUUUUCCGAAACAGAGCAGACAAAGUUGGCGAUGCUGUCGGGGAUUCUGCUGGGCAAUGGCACCCUGCCCGCCACCAUCCUCACCAGUCUCUUCACCGACAGCUUAGUCAAAGAAGGCAUUGCGGCCUCAUUUGCUGUCAAGCUUUUCAAAGCAUGGAUGGCAGAAAAAGAUGCCAACUCUGUUACCUCGUCUUUGAGAAAAGCCAACUUAGACAAGAGGCUGCUUGAACUCUUUCCAGUUAACAGACAGAGUGUGGAUCAUUUUGCUAAAUACUUCACUGACGCAGGUCUUAAGGAGCUUUCCGACUUCCUCCGAGUCCAGCAGUCCCUGGGCACCAGGAAGGAACUGCAGAAGGAGCUCCAGGAGCGUCUUUCUCAGGAAUGCCCGAUCAAGGAGGUGGUGCUUUAUGUCAAAGAAGAAAUGAAGAGGAAUGAUCUUCCAGAAACAGCAGUGAUUGGUCUUCUGUGGACAUGUAUAAUGAACGCUGUUGAGUGGAACAAGAAGGAAGAACUUGUUGCAGAGCAGGCUCUGAAGCACCUGAAGCAAUAUGCUCCCCUGCUGGCCGUGUUCAGCUCCCAAGGCCAGUCAGAGCUGAUCCUCCUCCAGAAGGUUCAGGAAUACUGCUACGACAACAUCCAUUUCAUGAAAGCCUUUCAGAAGAUUGUGGUUCUCUUUUAUAAAGCUGAUGUUCUGAGCGAAGAAGCAAUACUGAAAUGGUAUAAGGAAGCACAUGUUGCUAAAGGCAAAAGUGUUUUUCUUGACCAGAUGAAGAAAUUUGUUGAGUGGUUACAAAAUGCAGAAGAAGAAUCCGAAUCGGAAGGUGAGGAAAAUUAAAUGGCUCAACAAGCACAAUACCUAGGUUACCACACACCACUUUUUGAUUGGGAAUGCUGAACCAUUUGAGAAGAGAAACUUGGCUUCUGUUUUCGCAAAGGAAAAAAAAAAUAGGAUAGGCUUCCCUUGUGCAGAGGGAGAAAUGGUUUUGUUUUUGUUUUGUUUUUAAAUGGAGCCCUGAGGCAUCAGCUAUUAUACUUGGGACUCUACCUCUCACUCACUAUAUGCUAACUUAAAGCCAUUCAACAAGGAGUCAAGUAGAUCUGAAAUUAAAUACUCAACAGACUCCUCCUUUUUUAGCUGUAUUUUUCAGGUACUGUGUGGUGACCGCCCCACUGGUGUCUAUUACAGGCCACUUUGGUAGUUGUGUAUCUGCUCAUGUAUGUGAUUUGACAAACCAGUUUUUUAAAAUAAAUGGCUUUUUAAAAA